ACAGUCUCCAGCCUGAAGCGGAAGUGGAGGAAAGAUGGAGGACCAUCAGCACGUGCCCAUCGACAUCCAGACCAGCAAGCUGCUCGAUUGGCUGGUGGACAGAAGGCACUGCAGCCUGAAAUGGCAGAGUCUGGUGCUGACGAUCCGCGAGAAGAUCAAUGCUGCCAUCCAGGACAUGCCAGAGAGCGAAGAGAUCGCCCAGCUGCUGUCUGGGUCCUACAUUCACUACUUUCACUGCCUAAGAAUCCUGGACCUUCUCAAAGGCACAGAGGCCUCCACGAAGAAUAUUUUUGGCCGAUACUCUUCACAGCGGAUGAAGGAUUGGCAGGAGAUUAUAGCUCUGUAUGAGAAGGACAACACCUACUUAGGUAAAGUGGCCCGGCCUGGGAGCCCUGGUAUCCAUGGGGAAGCCCACUCUCAGAGUUCUGAGAUACCAGGCUUAUAGGAGGCACAGUCUGUGAGUGGGAAGAGACUGGAGUGUAGAUGUUGCCCAUUUGUAGGUGGUAAAAUCAAUUGUUUUUGAUGGAAUUGAUUUUCCCUGAGUGGAGUGCUGGGGGAAGGAGGAGGUCCAGGCCGGUAGUGGCCAUUCGCCGUGCCUCAGCGAGCAGGUGUGUGUGGGUCCUCCACCACUCACCUCUUGGUUAGCGGGAGUGUGCUGCCCCCACCCCCACCCCCGCACCCCCAUUCUACACAAGGCAGAAGAGGCACGGGUUUUUCUGGGAGCGAAUAUCAAGUGCCUGAGAGCAACUACAGGACUAACUGUGUUUGGGUUGGGUGUAGUAUAAAUAAUAAUAAUGGCUAAUAUUUCCUGAGCAUCUACUAAAUGCAAGGAAUUGUGCUUGGUGUGUCAUGUGGAUUCUCUCUUGCAUCUUCAUGAUAAAUGUUAUUGUCGCUGUUUUACCGAUGAGGGUUGGAUUAGAGGGGUUAAACAACUUGUCUUAGGCUCCACAGCUGGGAACAAGUGGGGCUGGGAAGCUGACUUCGUGCUCUUCACCACCACAAAGGAUGUGUGUGCAUCCUGGGGCAUGCCUGCCUCAUGUGGGGGUGUCCUGGGCUGAAUUUCCUGGGCACUUCUCAGUGGAACUCUCUAGCCUCCUGGUUCGGAAUGUCAACUAUGAGAUCCCCUCACUGAAGAAGCAGAUUGCCAAGUGCCAGCAGCUGCAGCAAGAAUACAGCCGCAAGGAGGAGGAGUGCCAGGCAGGGGCUGCCGAGAUGCGGGAGCAGUUCUACCACUCCUGCAAGCAGUAUGGCAUCACGGGCGAAAAUGUCCGAGGAGAACUGCUGGCCCUGGUGAAGGACCUGCCGAGUCAGCUGGCUGAGAUUGGGGCAGCGGCUCAGCAGUCCCUGGGGGAAGCCAUUGACGUGUACCAGGCGUCUGUGGGGUUUGUGUGUGAGAGGUAGAGAGGCCUCAGCUUCUCCUGGUGGGGGUGCUUUGCCUGUGUUCCCCAGCUCAUGACCCUUCUCCAGUUGUCUUGUUCCCAUAUAACAUUUGAACUCUUUACACACCUGAACCUGUGGGGGCCUUGCCCAUUUGACCAUGUGGCCCAGGCCAAAGCCCAGUGUUGGCCUUACGCAUGGUCGGCAGGAGAGUCAGUUGUGUGCUCUGUUGAAGCCCCACAGAGCAGGUGUUGCCAAUGCUGCGGUUCGUGCAGAAGCGGGGAAACUCAACGGUGUACGAGUGGAGGACAGGGACAGAGCCCUCUGUGGUGGAACGACCCCACCUCGAGGAGCUUCCUGAGCAGGUGGCAGAAGAUGCGAUUGACUGGGGCGACUUUGGGGUAGAGGCAGUGUCUGAGGGGACUGACUCUGGCAUCUCUGCCGAGGCUGCUGGAAUCGACUGGGGCAUCUUCCCGGAAUCAGAUUCAAAGGAUCCUGGAGGUGAUGGGAUAGACUGGGGAGACGAUGCUGUUGCUUUGCAGAUCACAGUGCUGGAAGCAGGAACCCAGGCUCCAGAAGGUGUUGCCAGGGGCCCAGAUGCCCUGACACUGCUUGAAUACACUGAGACCCGGAAUCAGUUCCUUGAUGAGCUCAUGGAGCUUGAGAUCUUCUUAGCCCAGAGAGCAGUGGAGUUGAGUGAGGAGGCAGAUGUCCUGUCUGUGAGCCAGUUCCAGCUGGCUCCAGCCAUCCUGCAGGGCCAGACCAAAGAGAAGAUGGUUACCAUGGUGUCAGUGCUGGAGGAUCUGAUUGGCAAGCUUACCAGUCUUCAGCUGCAACACCUGUUUAUGAUCCUGGCCUCACCAAGGUAUGUGGACCGAGUGACUGAAUUCCUCCAGCAAAAGCUGAAGCAGUCCCAGCUGCUGGCUUUGAAGAAAGAGCUGAUGGUGCAGAAGCAGCAGGAGGCACUUGAGGAGCAGGCGGCUCUGGAGCCUAAGCUGGACCUGCUACUGGAGAAGACCAAGGAGCUGCAGAAGCUGAUUGAAGCUGACAUCUCCAAGAGGUACAGCGGGCGCCCUGUGAACCUGAUGGGAACCUCUCUGUGACACCCUCCGUGUUCUUGCCUGCCCAUCUUCUCCGCUUUUGGGAUGAAGAUGAUAGCCAGGGCUGUUGUUUUGGGGCCCUUCAAGGCAAAAGACCAGGCUGACUGGAAGAUGGAAAGCCACAGGAAGGAAGCGGCACCUGAUGGUGAUCUUGGCACUCUCCAUGUUCUCUACAAGAAGCUGUGGUGAUUGGCCCUGUGGUCUAUCAGGCGAAAACCACAGAUUCUCCUUCUAGUUAGUAUAGCGGACUUAAUAAAAGAGGAAAAAACUCUUGCUUCAGUA